GGCCCCCUGCUGCCGUUGUCUUUACGGAACCUUUGGUGUCGGGGCUUGGAAGUCUCCUUGGCGCCGGCUUCUGGGCCCGGGCGAAGCUGGUGCGUGGCGCCGGGGUGGAGGCGGCUAAGUCCCAGGGACUUCUGCCCUGCGCCUCCGACGGGCAUUUGUCUGGCUGCGUCCGGGCUCGGGACGAUCCUGGGUCCUCGCUGGCGCUGCGGCCCUGCCCGGCGGCUUCGUGACCUCCGGCGGCGAAUCCCCGGGCUCGCGCAACGAGUUGUAGCCGCGGAGAGCAGGCGUCGAUGCUGGCGCCCAAAGCCUCCAGCCUGAGAGUCGCCUCACUCGUGUGACGGUGCUUAGAAACCCCCUUUUUUGGUUUUGUCUUUAAGUACUGUCUAGGGAAACGAAUCAUUUGAAGCAGUUUAUGCCUUUUUUGUUUUUUUCGAAGAGAAAGAUUUAUGCCGGACUGAAAAAUAGCGAAUCAAGUAUUUAGUGACCGUGUGAUAUUGCAGUAAAGACUGCCUCCACGUUGGACAUGUAGUGGAUUCUAGUUCAGGCUCUCCUGCAACAUGUUUUUGUUUCAAUUCUUUUACAAUUUAAAGCAUAUGCUUAUUUUAAUGAGAACGAAAAAGAAAGCUUAACUCUUUUUAAACUCGUUAAAAAUGGAGUUAUUUACUGUAAAGACGUCUUACAGCAAUUAGGAAGAAUAUACAUUGCAUGAAAGGCCUUUUGAAACGUUUAUCUAUUUGAUGAUUGCUGACUGCCUGUUACAGAGUUUCACUCCUGUUACCCAGGCUGGAGGACAAUGAUGUGAUCUCGGGUCACCACAACCUCCGCCUCCCGGAUUCAAGCGAUUCUCAUGCCUCAGCCUCCCGAGUAGCUCAGAUUACAGGCAUGUGCCACCACGCCCGGCUAAUUUUGUAUUUUCAGUCGAGACGGGGUUUCCCCAUGUUGGUCAGGCUAGUCUUGAAUUCCCGACCUCAGGUGAUCUGUUCGCCUCGGCCUCCCAAAGUGCUGGGAUUACAGGCGUGAACCACUGCACCCGGCGAGGCAUUUUUUACUGUCUACAGAAACUUAUUGUAAUUCAUUUUUCCUCACUCCAGUAGUAAGAAUUAUACCAAAUUGAAAAGAUAUGAAUGAGUAUCCUAAAAAAAGAAAAAGGAAGACUCUACACCCUUCUCGUUAUUCAGAUUCCUCUGGAAUAAGCAGAAUUGCAGAUGGAUUCAAUGGAAUUUUCUCUGAUCAUUGUUACAGUGUCUGUUCUAUGAGACAGCCAGAUUUAAAAUAUUUUGACAACAAAGAUGAUGAUUCUGAUACCGAGACGUCAAAUGACUUGCCAAAAUUUGCAGAUGGAAUCAAGGCCAGAAACAGAAAUCAGAACUACCUGGUUCCCAGUCCUGUACUUAGAAUUCUAGACCACACUGCCUUUUCUACAGAAAAAUCUGCUGAUAUUGUAAUUUGUGAUGAAGAGUGUGACUCACCUGAAUCAGUCAACCAGCAAACCCAAGAGGAGAGUCCUAUAGAAGUUCACACUGCUGAAGAUGUUCCAAUUGCUGUAGAAGUGCAUGCGAUUUCUGAGGAUUAUGAUAUAGAGACAGAAAACAAUUCCUCUGAGAGUCUCCAAGACCAAACUGAUGAAGAACCGCCAGCUAAACUUUGUAAAAUUCUUGACAAGAGCCAAGCUUUGAAUGUGACUGCCCAGCAGAAAUGGCCUUUACUGAGAGCUAAUAGCAGUGGCCUCUAUAAAUGUGAACUUUGUGAGUUUAACAGCAAAUAUUUUUCUGACUUAAAGCAGCAUAUGAUCCUGAAGCAUAAACGUACUGAUUCAAAUGUGUGUCGAGUAUGCAAGGAAAGUUUCUCUACCAAUAUGCUUCUGAUAGAACAUGCCAAACUGCAUGAAGAGGAUCCCUACAUUUGUAAAUACUGUGAUUAUAAGACAGUAAUUUUUGAGAACCUCAGCCAGCACAUUGCAGACACCCAUUUUAGUGAUCACCUCUAUUGGUGUGAACAGUGUGAUGUACAGUUCUCCUCAAGCAGUGAACUCUACCUACAUUUCCAGGAGCACAGCUGUGAUGAACAGUACUUGUGUCAGUUCUGUGAACAUGAAACUAAUGAUCCAGAAGACUUGCAUAGCCAUGUGGUAAAUGAGCAUGCAUGUAAAUUAAUAGAGUUAAGUGAUAAGUAUAACAAUGGUGAACAUGGACAGUAUAGCCUCUUAAGCAAAAUUACCUUUGACAAAUGUAAAAACUUCUUUGUAUGUCAAGUAUGUGGUUUUCGGAGUAGACUUCACACAAAUGUUAACAGGCAUGUUGCUAUUGAACAUACAAAAAUUUUUCCUCAUGUUUGUGAUGACUGUGGGAAAGGCUUUUCAAGUAUGCUAGAAUAUUGCAAGCAUUUAAAUUCACAUUUAUCUGAAGGGAUUUAUUUAUGUCAAUAUUGUGAAUAUUCAACAGGACAAAUUGAAGAUCUUAAAAUUCAUCUAGAUUUCAAGCAUUCAGCUGACUUGCCUCAUAAAUGUAGUGACUGCUUGAUGAGGUUUGGAAAUGAAAGGGAAUUAAUAAGUCACCUUCCAGUCCAUGAGACAACUUGAUUAUUCUCUUUAACUUACAGAAUGUUAGUUUAAAAUAAUAAAUUCAUCCUUUUUUUGGAGAUGAUUAAAUGGAUGAUUGUAAACACAACUUAUGAAAUCUGCCUUUAACAAGUAACUUUUUUAAAUUAUAAAAUUUUAUUGGCAUUGCUCCAUUUUCUGUAUAUAAAUAUAUCUUUAAUGUGGUAUUUUCAAUUGCGUGAUAGUUUGUAGUUUCAACCACUCUUGGUGACUGUCAUCCUGUUUCUUCCAUAUUCUCUGAUUUCAUGAAUUGAAAAGAAACAAAUGUAUUGAAGAAGUGAGCUACAGUUUUCCUUCCUUAACCAUGGGUGCUAGUAACUUUUUAAAACUCAAGACAAGAUUAGUUUUUUAUGUGUGAAGUCAUUAAAUUAUUACACGACCAGAACUAAAAUGCAAUAUACAGUUAAGUCCACGGAUACUCCCAUUAAUGAGAAAUAACACUAGGAAGCCACUAUUACAGGAAGAAAAGAUUUGGUUUUCAUGGCAGUCUGUUUUUUUAAAAAAAAAUUUUUGAGCCACUAUCUAUUGUUGAAUAUUUUAAGAUGGGAUGAGGGAGGAACUAAUAAGGGCUUACACAAUAAAAAAUAACUAUAUCAUAACUCAUUCAUAACUUGAUGUUUCAUUUUCUGUUGAGGAACCAUAAAUUCAUUCACAGACUUAAUAUUUUUUUCUUAGAGAUGGUCUCGUUCUGUUGUCCAGGAUGGAGUGCAGUGGUUGAUCAUAGCUCCCGGGCUGUAGUCUCCCAGGCUCGAGCAAUCCUCCCACUUCACCCUCCUGCAUAGCUAGGACUACAGGCAUGUGGCACCAUGCCCGCUAAGUUUUUAAAUUUCUUGUAGAGAUGAGAUCUCGCUAUGUUGCCCAGGCCAGUCUCAAACUCCUGGACUCAAGCAAUCCUCCCACCUUGGCCUUCCAAAUCACUGGGAUUAUAGGCAUGAGCCAUUAUGCCUGACUCUUGCCCAAAUUUCUGAUGUCAAAUUGUUCAUUGACAGAAAACCCACUGAAGUAUUUAAAGUUAGGAAGAUCUGGGAGAUAGGGGUUGCUGGCAUGAAAAUGUAUAACUUACAACAUUUAUUAAUAAAAUGAUAAAUUAGCAUCAAUAUUAGUUCGUAUGGCUGCCAUAACAAAUUACUACAAACUGAGUUGCCUACCUAGCAGAAAUUUAUGGUCUCACAGUUGUGAAGGCCAGACAUUCAAAAUGGAGUUAUUGGCAGUUGGUUCCUUCUGAGGGUUGUGGGGGAAGGAUCUGUUUCAGGUCUGUCCUUGGCUUGUAGAUGGAUAGCCUCAUGUUCACAUGGUGUUCUCCCUGUGUGCAAGUCUGUCCCCCAAAUUUCCUCUUUUUUUUUUUUUUUUUGCUUUUUUAAUUUUUUGAGACAGAAUUUCACUCUUGUCGCCCAGGCUGGAGUACAGUGGCGCGAUCUCAGCUCAUUGCAACCUCCGCCUCCCAGGUUCAAGUGAUUCUGCUGCCUCAGCUUCCCAAGUAGCUGGGGUUAACAGGCGUCAGCCACCAUGCCAGGCUAAUUUUGUAUUUUUAGUAGAAACGGGGUUUCACCACGUUGGCCAGGCUGGUCUCAAAUUCCUGACCUCAGGUGAUCCACCUGCCUCAGUCUCCCAAAGUGCUGGGAUUACAGGCAUGAGGCACCGCCCCAGGCCAAAUUUCUUGUUUUUAUAAAGACUCCAGUCAUAUUGAUUGGAUUAGGGCCCCUCCCAAUGUCCUCCUUUUAACUUAAAGACCUGAUCUCCAAAUAAGGUCAUAUUCUAAGGUGCUGAGGUUUAGGACUUCAACAUAUGAAUUUGGGAGGGAACACAAUUGAGUAGCAGAGUCUGAAACAGCACUAUAAAGAAGAUAGAAUUAUAUGUAUCAUUGCCCUCAAAUUUAACAAGCACUGCUAACAUUAUUUUUUAGGUUUAUUGAUAUAAGUGGAAGAUCAAUUUAUGACCAAUGAUUUUCCCACUUCAAGAAUUUAGUCUGUUUGGACAAUGGUGGCUGCAAGUAUUCUUAGAAGGUAUUAUUUUUAUCCCCACUAUUUUGUUGUAUGUGCAUACCUGUGUUCCUAGCAACUCACAUUCCAUCUAAUUAUAACAUUCCUGUUACGGCUGAUAACAAAUGUUUCUCAGAAGACUUAAAAUUGUAACAGUUUAAAUUGUAAGAUAACCUUAGAAAGCAUCUGGUCUAAACCCUCCAGUUUUCUAAGUUCCUUGCAGAAAUAGAAAUGUAGAUAGCUAUGAGGCCAAGUACAUAUAACCAGUUAUGUCUCAUGGGAGUGGGAUCCAGGUUAUCUGGUUUACUGUCUAGUGAUGUUUCCAUUACAUCAUGUUACAUAAACCUAACCUUUCUCCCUGGGAUGUUUUUUGUGACUACUUCACCUAACAAUUAACCUAGUUGUUGAUAAUUUUGUUUUUAUGCUUUUUAUACAUCUAGCUCCAGGAAUUGGAUUUUUGGAAAAACACCUUAAGUAAUGCCUUGGUUUGUUUGUUUUCUUUUAAUCUAUUUGCUGCUUUACAUUUGGAUCAAGUGUUAGUAAUUGAAAAGAUUGCAGGCUGGGCGUGGUGGCCCACGCCUCUAAUCCCAGCACUUUGUGGGUGGCUGAGAUGGGCAGAUCACGAGGUCAGGAGAUCCAGACCAUCCUGGCUAACAGUGAAACCCCGUCUCUACUAAAAAUACAAAAAAAAAUUAGCUGGGCGUGGUGGUGGGCACCUGUAGUCCCAGCUACUCGGGAGGCUGAGGCAGGAGAAUGGCGUGAACCCGGGAGGUGGAGCUUGCAGUGAGCCGAGAUCGCGCCACCACAUUCCAGCCUGGGUGACAGAGUGAGACUGUCUCAAAAAAAAAAAAGAAAAGAAGAAAAGAUUGCAAUGCAGCUACUCAAGAGACAUAUAUCCAAGUUUCAGAACCAUAUAAUUUUGUACUUUUUUUUUUUUCAGACAGUCUUGCUCUGUUGCCCAGGCUGGAGUGUAGUGGCGUGAUCUUGGCUCAAGGCAACCUCCACCUCUCAGGUGUAAGCAAUUCUCCUGCCUUAGCCUCCCAAGUAGCUGGGAUUAUAGGCGUGUGCCACCACACCCGGCUAAUUUUUGUGUUUUUAAUAGAGACGGGGUUUCACCAUGUUGACCAGGCUGGUCUUGAACUCCUGACCUCUUGUGAUCUGCCCACCUCGACCUCCCAAAGUGCUAGGAUUACAGGCGUGAGCCACUGCACCCGGCAUAAUUUUGGACUUUUUGAUGAAUCUGCAGCUUCAGGACCUAUCCCAAUGACAGUUUGUCCCACAAAACCUUUUCGCCUUGGCCCAGUUUUCAAAUCAAUGAUUGACCAUAAAUUGCUUGAAGUAGUUGGUCUUUAUUUAUUUAUUUUUUGAGAUGGAGCCUUGCUCUGUCGCCCAGACUGGAAUGCAGUGGCGUGAUCUUGGCUCGCUGCAACCUCUGCCUCCCGGGUUUAAGCAAUUCUCCUGCCUCAGCCUCCCGAGUAGCUGGGAUACAGGUGCCCACCACCACACCCAGCUAAUUUUUCUAUUUUUAGUAGAGAUGGGGUUUCACCAUCUUGGCCAGGCUGGUCUUGAACUCCUGACCUUGUGAUCCACCCACUUCGGCCUCCCAAAGUGCUGGGAUUACAGGCCUGAGCCACCACGCCCGGCCAGUCUUUAUUUUUAACUUAAAGAACUUCAGAAAAACAAACCUACCUAAAAAAAUUAACACUCCUGGUUUUGUUUUGUUUUUUGUUUUGUUUUACUUCAGAGACAGACAUUUUCACUGUAUACUUGUGACUUGCACCACAAUUCAAGUCUGAGAUUACCUAACUGAUGAUGUUUAUUAACACUUCAGUAGAAUUCUUCGCAGCAGUGAACAGUAGUGACAGGUCAUUAUGUUUUUCUUGCUGUUUUAAAUCUUCAUCUUACAAUGAGUUAUUUUGAAAUUCCAAAACAUUUCCCUGUAUUCCAGAAAUUGAAAAUGGUUGUUCACUAAAAAGCCUCUUCUUUUCCUGCUUAUAAAUUUGCCAAUUUUGCCAUUUUAAAUCACCUUUCUUACGUUUCUCUGAAUUGUAUAUUAUUUGUCAAUUUCACAGUUUCUAUAAUCUAUUGUUUGCUGAAUUGUUACAGUCUUUUGUUUUUAAUAGACUAGCACUAUUCCUAAUUAUUAAAUCUGAUUUACAAAGCA